GGUGCUUUGUGUGCUGCCGGCGGGGCGCGCGGCGGUCCGGGCGGGUGACUGGCGGCGGGCGCCGCGGUCGGGCUGGCUGCCGGGCAGCAUGGAGGAGCUGAGCAGCGUGGGCGAGCAGGUCUUCGCCGCCGAGUGCAUCCUGAGCAAGCGGCUCCGCAAGGGCAAGCUGGAGUACCUGGUCAAGUGGCGCGGCUGGUCCUCCAAACAUAACAGCUGGGAGCCGGAGGAGAACAUCCUGGACCCGAGGCUGCUCCUGGCCUUCCAGAAGAAGGAACAUGAGAAGGAGGUGCAGAACCGGAAGAGAGGCAAGAGGCCGAGAGGCCGGCCAAGGAAGCUCACUGCCAUGUCCUCCUGCAGCCGGCGCUCCAAGCUCAAGGAACCCGAUGCUCCCUCCAAAUCCAAGUCCAGCAGUUCCUCCUCUUCCUCCACGUCAUCCUCCUCUUCCUCAGAUGAAGAGGAUGACAGUGACUUAGAUGCUAAGAGGGGUCCCCGGGGCCGCGAGACCCACCCAGUGCCGCAGAAGAAGGCCCAGAUCCUGGUGGCCAAACCCGAGCUGAAGGAUCCCAUCCGGAAGAAGCGGGGACGAAAGCCCCUGCCCCCAGAGCAAAAGGCAACCCGAAGACCCGUGAGCCUGGCCAAGGUGCUGAAGACCGCCCGGAAGGAUCUGGGGGCCCCGGCCAGCAAGCUGCCCCCUCCACUCAGCGCCCCCGUUGCAGGCCUGGCAGCUCUGAAGGCCCACGCCAAGGAGGCCUGUGGCGGCCCCAGUGCCAUGGCCACCCCAGAGAACCUGGCCAGCCUAAUGAAGGGCAUGGCCAGUAGCCCCGGCCGGGGUGGCAUCAGCUGGCAGAGCUCCAUCGUGCACUACAUGAACCGGAUGACCCAGAGCCAGGCCCAGGCUGCCAGCAGGUUGGCGCUGAAGGCCCAGGCCACCAACAAGUGCGGCCUCGGGCUGGACCUGAAGGUGAGGACGCAGAAAGGGGAGCUGGGAAUGAGCCCUCCAGGAAGCAAAAUCCCGAAGGCCCCCAGCGGUGGGGCUGUGGAGCAGAAAGUGGGGAACACAGGGGGCCCCCCGCACACCCAUGGUGCCAGCAGGGUGCCUGCUGGGUGCCCAGGCCCCCAGCCAGCACCCACCCAGGAGCUGAGCCUCCAGGUCUUGGACUUGCAGAGUGUCAAGAAUGGCAUGCCCGGGGUGGGUCUCCUUGCCCGCCACGCCACCGCCACCAAGGGUGUCCCGGCCACCAACCCAGCCCCUGGGAAGGGCACUGGGAGUGGCCUCAUUGGGGCCAGCGGGGCCACCAUGCCCACCGACACAAGCAAAAGUGAGAAGCUGGCUUCCAGAGCAGUGGCGCCACCCACCCCUGCCAGCAAGAGGGACUGUGUCAAGGGCAGUGCUACCCCCAGUGGGCAGGAGAGCCGCACAGCCCCCGGAGAAGCCCGCAAGGCGGCCACACUGCCAGAGAUGAGCGCAGGUGAGGAGAGUAGCAGCUCGGACUCCGACCCCGACUCCGCCUCGCCGCCCAGCACUGGACAGAACCCGUCAGUGUCCGUUCAGACCAGCCAGGACUGGAAGCCCACCCGCAGCCUCAUCGAGCACGUAUUUGUCACCGACGUCACUGCCAACCUCAUCACCGUCACAGUGAAGGAGUCUCCCACCAGCGUGGGCUUCUUCAACCUGAGGCAUUACUGAAGCCCCGGCGCCACCAGCUGCGCGGUCUUACUCCCCUUCCCUGCCUAUGGUGUCGCUUGGCUAAGUGACUCCCAGCCCAAGCCCCCUCAAGAGUCUGGGUCGGGGGAGGAGGAGUGGGUGGCCUCCUUGAUGGGCAGGCUUGGAAGGGACUUCUCCCGCACCCCACUCUGUCCCAGGACAUAGGGCAGGGGGCCUCACUGCCUUGUUGGUCUCCACCUUGUUCCUACCUCUGCAGGCCUCUUUGCUCUCCCCUCUUGCCUCAGGAAACCCGGUGGCACCUGUGGCUCCAGGUGACUGUCUUGAACAGAGCGGGCUUCUUCAUGGCUGCGUUGUUGCUGAGUUUGAACUGCUCCUCCCUGGCCUGCGUGACUGAAUCACAGCUUUGGUCCCUGUCUUGCAGGGGCUGAGGUGUCAGGAGGGGACUUCUGGCCCACCUUGCCUUCAGCCCUGGAGUGGGCAGAGAGUAUUGUGGGGAGGCAUGGCCAGUGGGACUAGUGUUCCCUCCAUCUGGCCACAGCUUUUGGGAGAUGGGGUGGGCAGGGGUGGUCCUGGCUGGCAUUGCCUGAGCCGGCAGUGAUGAAGUGGGGAGCUUGCCCUUGACAGGUGGGGGCUGGCUGGGGCCUUAAUGUGAAAAGACAGUGGCAGGCAGCUGGAGUAGAGCGAGCCCAGCAGCCCUAAAAGGCUGCCUUCAUGGCCAUCUAGCCCCAGUUCAGGGCAGCAUCCAUAGCCCACAAGCCAGCGUGGGUGGGGCGGGGGUGGUCCCACAGCUGGGUUCCACCUGAAGAGCCUCCGUGCCUCGGAGCAGGAGAGGCAGGCUAUGGCUGCCACCCUCCCUCCUGCCUGUGUCCCAGUGAGAACUGACCUGAGUCCCCUUCCAAACCCAGACCCACCUCCUGCCCCAGGCCCACUGAAGCAUGUUCCAUUUCUAAAAAGCCCAGAGUUCAGUGUGUCCCAAGGAAAACCCAAAGUGGAGGUGCUCAGGUCCAGGGGAGUCCAGUGGGCAGGACCCUUGGCAGGCAAGCCCCUCCCUUCACUCCCAGGACCUACCUUCUGCUAGUAAAGGACUGGCUUCAUUCUAAUUAUGGCCCACAGACUGCCCCGGAGACCUGGAGGACAGCAGUGCUGGCACUUGGGUGUCCAUGGGCCCGUCUGCCGGCUCUGCCUGUGCUGCAAGUGUUGGCCGUGGGUCCAGCCAACAACUCCCUACGUCCUGUGUGGGGCCCUGCCCAAGUGGAUGAGGCAUUCCUUGAGGAGUAUCAUUUUCCCUGACAAUCCCCAUCACCUUUAGGGGUUCCCUGCUUGGCUCCUUUCCAGCUGAAAAACUAGACCUGUGCCAUUGGGGAAGCUGGACAAAGUCUAGGGGGCCCGCCUGGUAGAGGGUCCCGGGAAGCUGGAUCUGUCAGCCUCGGCCCUGAGGCCCCUGUUAACUCAAGACUGUGAGCUGCCUCUAGGUGGUCACGUCUGGGAGCUAGCUUGUAUGGCUUCUGACCAGUAUCAGGAUUUCUGUUCUGAGAGCAGCGUGGGCAGCAAGGCAGGGCAGCCCAGAGGUGGCAGCGGCAGGCAAUCUGGUCACUAGGUCUUUGUGAUGCCAAAAAUAAAAGAGGGUGGGGUGGGUGCUUUCUGUUCCUCUGAUUGGAUGGAGUCCGCCAGCAGGCAUGGGGCUACAUUCCAGUGCCUGACUAUAGGGAGGCACUCCUGAUUCCAUGGAGCAGCCCGGACUUUGAGAAUGGGCUCUGGUUUGCGGGGGGCAGGCGUACCAGACUGCAAGACCCCCCAGUACCUCACCGUGCCAAAUAGGAAGAGGUGGCCUUGGUGUAGCCAAAUGGAUCUUUUUAACAGUGUGCCUUUGGGGAGGGACCCAUGUCCAUGGCUUCGUUGAGGGCCAUCCAUAUGCCAGCUGGGGGCCAGCCCACAGUGGCCAUAUUGGCUGCAGCAGGAAUGGUGCCCACCUCGGCGAAUUGAAGGGCUAAGAGUCCCAGAUAGCUAGGCCAGAGCUGGAAGCAGACAGUAAGGGGAAGAGCUGCUCCCACAGGAGAGGGAGAGAUUCCAGCUCACUGCGCAGCCUGGGAGGAGGCGUGGAUCCUGGCACGCUGAGCCUCAGGCACCAGCCUCCCUGUGCUCGACAGCAAAGUCUUGACUCCUUCCUGCUGAGCACUGUGCUACCUUCACUGCUCCAAAGCCAGACUAACAGCUCUCCAAGCCCUUGGGGUGACUCGGCUUCCAGGAGCUGUUGGAGAAAUGAGGAUGUCUGUCCCUGUCUGCCUGGGCAGGCCAGAUUCCUCCCCAGCAGCCGGGUCUCUCCAGACCCUGAUUCGGUGCCUUUCUGUUUACCAGCUACUUCAAUCCCAAAGUUUGAAUCUGCAGAUACCUUACUCCCAGCCACUUUGCCUUCUUACUGUGUUGUGUGUUUUUCCUGGUGCUUCAAGAGCGUGUGCAGGGCAAGUGCCGUCACUGGGAACUGCACCAGAUGCUCAGACUUGGUUGUCUUAUGUUUACCAAUAAAUAAAAGUAGACUUUUUCUAUUUUUAUUUGCUGCUAUUUGUGUGUGUGUUUGUGUUUGUGUAGCUAGGUAUCUGGCACUUCUGACGAUGCAUUGUUGCUUUUUUCCCGAAGGUCCCGCAGGAACUGUGGCAAUGGUGUGUGUGUGAAAUGGUGUGUUAACCGCGUUUUGUUUGCUCCUGUAUUGAAUAGGAAGCAGUGGCCAGUCUGUCUUCCUUAGAGAUGUUAGCAUAUUUUUAUAUGUAUAUAUUUUGUACCAAAAAAGAGUGUUCCUUGUUUUGGUUACACUCGAAAUUCUGACCUAGCUGGAGAGGGCUCUGGGCCGAGAGCUUUCACUAAGGGGAGACUUCAGGGGAGGAUCAAGCUUUGAACCAAAGCCAAUCACUGGCUUGAUUUGUGUUUUUUAAUUAAAAAAAAAAUCAUUCAUGUAUGCCACUUCUAA